AACGUCAGCGCUUGAGGCUUGAAGAGGGAGACAAGCUAAAAGAGGAUAUCCAGUUGUUUCAUGAUGGCAUUUGCACCUCCAAAAAACACAGAUGGUCCCAAAAUGCAGACAAAGAUGAGCACCUGGACACCCCUAAACCAUCAGCUAUUGAAUGACCGGGUAUUUGAAGAAAGAAGAGCCCUGCUUGGCAAAUGGUUUGACAAAUGGACAGACUCUCAAAGAAGAAGAAUCCUCACAGGCCUGUUGGAGCGCUGCUCGCUGUCCCAGCAAAAGUUCUGCUGUCGAAAGCUUCAAGAGAAAAUUCCAGCAGAAGCCCUGGACUUUACAACCAAGCUUCCAAGGGUGUUAUCUUUAUACAUCUUUUCUUUCCUGGACCCUCGGAGCCUUUGUCGUUGUGCACAGGUGUGCUGGCAUUGGAAGAACCUUGCUGAGCUGGACCAGCUCUGGAUGCUGAAAUGUUUACGGUUUAACUGGUACAUCAAUUUCUCUCCAACUCCCUUUGAGCAGGGGAUCUGGAAGAAGCACUAUAUUCAAAUGGUGAAAGAACUUCAUAUUACCAAGCCUAAGACACCCCCAAAGGAUGGAUUUGUAAUCGCUGACGUUCAACUAGUUACAAGCAAUUCUCCAGAGGAAAAACAGUCCCCUUUAUCAGCUUUUCGGUCCUCUUCCUCUUUAAGAAAGAAGAAUAACUCAGGGGAGAAAGCACUUCCACCCUGGCGAUCUUCUGAUAAGCACCCAACAGAUAUCAUUCGUUUUAAUUACCUAGACAACCGUGACCCCAUGGAGACUGUCCAGCAAGGAAGAAGAAAAAGAAACCAAAUGACCCCAGACUUCAGCCGACAGUCACAUGAUAAGAAAAAUAAAUUGCAGGACAGAACUAGGCUAAGAAAAGCACAAUCAAUGAUGUCGAGGAGAAAUCCCUUCCCACUAUGUCCCUAAGUGCCAGCUCUCCCCUAAAAGUUCCAGCUCAUCUCGCCUGGCCUCCCCCUGAGUCAGUGGGACUCCCAGACACUGCCACCACAGCUGAAAUUCUCAUGCAGCAUCCUCACAGGCACCCUGGGCCCCAAGCAUGACUCAUCCAGGUUCCAGAGCCAAAGUGGACUGAACAUGGAAAGACUUUUAUUAUAGAAAUGACAAGAUGCUUUGCACAGUGGAGAGCUGAAUUUACUUGGCUCCCAUUAGAAACUCUUUCAGCUUAAGUACUUAUUGUGGUAGUGAGUCCUACGGUAUUUCAGUAAAAAGGAAUUCAUGGCA